AGAGUCAAUUUCGAGAUGUAAAUGCGAUUGCAGCAUGGAAUGGAAAAGGUGCAGUCAUAUUGCCUGGGCUUUAUUUUUACCCAGGUUAAACUCAUAUACUUCAUGAUUUCCAUUGUAAUCCAGAUGCCAUUGAUGCUGUUAAAGUUGUUUAUUUUUAAUUUGUAUUGAGGAAUGAGAGCACACUUGGGAUUCAAUUCAAAAUAUAACAGAAACAAUGUAAUUGAAAUUGCCUUUAAUAUUCAUUUCUUGUUUUUGUAAGGUAUGCCUGUAUUUCACGGGGUUUAAUACAUUGUUUGAUAUCCUGUUAUUUUUCUAAAUUAUAUUUGAGUUGAUUUCUAUCCAGGUUGGACUUGUAUGAGAAUGUUGAAAGACGUUGACCUUUGAUCACAGACAUUACAAUAUGAAUUUUUCAGUUUCAAAAUGAAUUUUUAUUACUACUACCCCAGUUAUCUUUCACAUUUCUUUGUAAGUAACUUUACUGUAGUUAAAAAAAAAAAAAACACCCAAAACUGUUUCUCAUAUGGCUUUAAUAAUAGAGCAUAAACUUGUUUUUAUGAUAAGAAAGUUUACUAGAGAUUUGCUAGAUGCCAUUUGUUAUUAAUCUGUGCUUUGAGGACUCAGUUUCAUAGGACUCAGAAUGAUGUUUAUAAGCCUUUUAGUUAUCAGAACAUGAUGUCUUUUAUUAAUUAGCUUUUUAGGGGUCUUAAACUGUAAUUAACUGGCCUUCAAAUAAACACUACAAAUAAGCAUUUGAAAAUCCACUCUAUUCAUAAGGUAGAAAAUGACAUUUAUAAUCAUCCACUGACUGGAAAAGUGGAAAAAGAAAUUAAAAAGCCAAGUGAAGCAAGUUGGGAUGAUUCUACAUUAUCAUUAGAAACUUUCAAGAAUUUUCUCAGCCUGACUGUCCCCUUAGCCCACCAUUUUUGCCAUCAUUACACCAUGUUGCAUGUAUUACUUAUUCAUUGGGGAAUUUUCUACAACUGGGUUACUUUGUGAUUGUUGGUGUCCUUUUAAGAUUUCAGAUUAGUUGCUACACUGAUCAGUUAUCUUUUCAGAAGUUUCAAGAUAUUAAUAGUCCCCACAUUUAAGUUUCUAUAGAUUUUUAAAAAAUUAUUACUGUUCUGUUUUUCCCCCAUGUUACUACCCAUCUUUAGUGAGAGCUGUUCUUAUUUCUCAAGCUGUGCAGUUAAUUGGUCGUGCUAGCGUGUAUGUGCUUACUCUGUGCAGGCUUCAGAAUAAUUUAAUUGUGUAUUAAGUUUCAAACACUGACGACCUCUUAAAGAAGAAUGUUAAGUUAUACUAUUUCAUAUUUCAAUUACUUAAAUUACAUCAGUGAUGUAAUAAAAUGCAAUGUUGUCAUCGUAUUUAUUAAAUUUAAAUUUAAUUUUCAGCUAGUCCUUUGUCGAACUUGAAAUAUUUUCAUUUAUCAUAAACUGGAUCAGGCUUUGACACAUUUAUUUACAGAGGCACCCAAAUAGAAAAAGUAGGUCAAUUUGUUGCUAUGAUAGAAUAGAUUCUGGCAGUGUGCGAGAGUGUGUGUGUAUGUGUGUGUGUGCGUCUUGCCUGUCUUGAUCAAGUGCACAUUUCUCUCUAACUUUGGGGUAAGCUGCUUCUUGGGGACAGAAUGGCCCUUAGAGAGGUUUAACAUAGUUUUCUCAGCUUAAAAAUCCUUCUCUUUUUCAACGGGAUUAGAAAAUUCUCUUGCAACUUCGGUGUUUUCUGACUGAGUUUUUUCACUCCCCAUUUCCUCUGGGUUGUACAUGUAUAGUGAAUUCUUUUCUUAUUUCAUCUCUGCUUUUAAAUACUAGAUUGUUUUCUCAUCCAUGAAAAGAAGUAAAGCAUUUCAUUGACGCAGAUACUGUGAAUUUUACCCACAGGAAGAAAAUGUAGGGUUAACAUAUUGCUAGUAUUCAUACUUUAAAAGUAUAAAGAGAUGUGAAUUGAUUAAUUGAUUUGAUUUUUUCAUGAAAAUGACAUUUAUCUAAAAAAUAAGCAUCUGCUGUCUUACUGGAGAGGUGGCUUACAGUUUAACAUAACUUAGGUUUACCUUGAAGACAUUUUUUUUUCCUUUACUGUUAUCUGUAUUAUAUAACAGGGAGAAAACAAUACAUUCAGAGAGUAGAGGGAAAAUAAGAUAAUUCUAUAAUGUUUCCAAAUCAUUGGGCAUAUCAAAUAGUAUUUCAUCUUCUAUUGACAGAAUUUUAAAAACAAAAUAUAUAUUGCAAUUUGCAAUAAAACUUACCCUUUAUAGAUAAUUAAUAACAAAAUGUUCUCAGAGUAGAUUUUAAUGUUUAGACUAUUAGUAAGAUUUCAGAUGAUUGAAACAAAGCAUGUUUAUUCUUUUCUUUUGUGGAGCUUGGAUUGUUAAACAUUAGUUCUGGGAGAGACCAGGGAAGAUAAAGGUCUAUCAUAAACAUAACUAAUGAGAUAACUCCUCAAGGAUAAAUUUGGUCUAGAAUUAUUGUUAUGAGGUUAUAUUCUUUUAUAGAAUUUUCUAAAUCAAAUCUUGUACUUAAUUAAAAACAAUAGGGUAAUCUGACUUAAACUUUAAAAAUCUGGGCUUAUGAAAUAUAAUUCUUGCUAUAUAAUUCUUGCUUAGAGAAGUAGUGUGAUGGACUAUACAAAAGCAUUAAUUAGUGAUGGCACCUUCGGAGUAUGUAUGGAAAAAUAUGUCAACUGGUAGGUAAUAAUACCUGCUCUUAAAUUUCUCUUUUUUAUUUGUGUUUUCAAGGAGAGUCAUAUCAUCUAAUGUGUGUAAUGAAGUUAAUCGUGCUGAAUACACUAACAUCAUAGAAUUGGCAUGUAGUGUCAAUUAUUCACCAAAAAAGAAACUUAAGCAAUGACUAAUAUACCACAACAUUAGAUGUUGAUUUGAAAAGAUGAUGCAUAGAUGAAGUAAUUGUUAAAUUAAUCAUAAGGGAAAAUAUUGAGGCUUGAAAUAAAUUUGUUAGGUUAGCAUAAAUCCUGAGGCUUUUUGAAGGCAUCGUAAACUACUUUUGCAUUUGCUUUAAGUUCAUUGUUGAGGGGCAUAAGGAGAGCUCAGAGCCCAUCUGUGCCCAACUGCUGUGUGGUCUUGGGAAGGUCAGCCUGUCUUCUAGCUGAUUAAUCUGCAAAAUGAGAGGGUCAGAGAGACACUGUCCCCCGCCUCAUGUUGAAAACAGAUUACACUCUUGGAUUUGUUAAAAAAAAAAAAAAAAGAAGAAGAUCAUAGGUGACAAUGUCCACAGCUAUCAUAUUUCUUUUUCUCUAUUUAACAUAAUUAGAAUAGCCAGGAGGUUAAAAUUUUAGUAAAGAUAUGAAAAUUAAUAAAAUGUUUUCUCAAUUCAUAAAUAGUGCCAGAUCUGAAACAUCUAAGGAGGAUGGAGAAAAGUUCUAGAUAGUAUCUUUGCUGGCUAAAGAAGUUAAGACAGCAUCUAAGAGAAGUUAAGGAGCCAGGCGUGACGGCUCACGCCUGUAAUCCCAGCACUUUGGGAGGCUGUGGCAGGCGGAUCACCUGAGAUCGGGAGUUCAAGACCAGCCUGACCAACAUGGAGAAACCCCGUCUCUACUAAAAAUACAAAAUUAGUUGGGCAUGGUGGCGCAUGCCUGUAAUCCCAGCUACUUGGGAGGCUGAGGCAGGAGAAUCGCUUGAACCCAGGAGGUGGAAGUUGUGGUGAGCCAAGAUCGCGCCAUUGCACUCCAGCCUGGGCAACAAGAGCAAAACUCCUUCUCAAAAAGAAAAAAAAAAAAAAAGAAGAAGUAGUUAAGUUAGCAUAGUGCCUUACUGCGCCCAAAGUAACUUAGUAAAAGGAUAACGAAGGAGGCCCAACUUCAUUCAAUAAGGAGCCUGACGGAUUUAUCCCAGACGGUAGAACAAAAGGAAGAAUAUUGAUGGAUUUUAAACCAGAGUUUUUAAAGAGCUUGAGAAUACGGGGAAAUUAAUUUGUUCUCCUACACACAUAGAUAGGGUAAGGUUGUUUCUGAUGCAGCUGAGAAAAAUGCAGACCGUCAAAAAGGAGCAGGCGUCUCUUGAUGCCAGUAGCAAUGUGGACAAGAUGAUGGUCCUUAAUUCUGCUUUAACGGAAGUGUCAGAAGACUCCACAACAGGUGAGGAGCUGCUUCUCAGUGAAGGAAGUGUGGGGAAGAACAAAUCUUCUGCAUGUCGGAGGAAACGGGAAUUCAUUCCUGAUGAAAAGAAAGAUGCUAUGUAUUGGGAAAAAAGGCGGAAAAAUAAUGAAGCUGCCAAAAGAUCUCGUGAGAAGCGUCGACUGAAUGACCUGGUUUUAGAGAACAAACUAAUUGCACUGGGAGAAGAAAACGCCACUUUAAAAGCUGAGCUGCUUUCACUAAAAUUAAAGUUUGGUUUAAUUAGCUCCACAGCAUAUGCUCAAGAGAUUCAGAAACUCAGUAAUUCUACAGCUGUGUACUUUCAAGAUUACCAGACUUCCAAAUCCAAUGUGAGUUCAUUUGUGGACGAGCACGAACCCUCGAUGGUGUCAAGUAGUUGUAUUUCUGUCAUUAAACACUCUCCACAAAGCUCGCUGUCCGAUGUUUCAGAAGUGUCCUCAGUAGAACACACGCAGGAGAGCUCUGUGCAGGGAAGCUGCAGAAGUCCUGAAAACAAGUUCCAGAUUAUCAAGCAAGAGCCGAUGGAAUUAGAGAGCUACACAAGGGAGCCAAGAGAUGACCGAGGCUCUUACACAGCGUCCAUCUAUCAAAACUAUAUGGGGAAUUCUUUCUCUGGGUACUCACACUCUCCCCCACUACUGCAAGUCAACCGAUCCUCCAGCAACUCCCCGAGAACGUCGGAAACUGAUGAUGGUGUGGUAGGAAAGUCAUCUGAUGGAGAAGACGAGCAACAGGUCCCCAAGGGCCCCAUCCAUUCUCCAGUUGAACUCAAGCAUGUGCAUGCAACUGUGGUUAAAGUUCCAGAAGUGAAUUCCUCUGCCUUGCCACACAAGCUCCGGAUCAAAGCCAAAGCCAUGCAGAUCAAAGUAGAAGCCUUUGAUAAUGAAUUUGAGGCCACGCAAAAACUUUCCUCACCUAUUGACAUGACAUCUAAAAGACAUUUCGAACUCGAAAAGCAUAGUGCCCCAAGUAUGGUACAUUCUUCUCUUACUCCUUUCUCAGUGCAAGUGACUAACAUUCAAGAUUGGUCUCUCAAAUCGGAGCACUGGCAUCAAAAAGAACUGAGUGGCAAAACUCAGAAUAGUUUCAAAACUGGAGUUGUUGAAAUGAAAGACAGUGGCUACAAAGUUUCUGACCCAGAGAACUUGUAUUUGAAGCAGGGGAUAGCAAACUUAUCUGCAGAGGUUGUCUCACUCAAGAGACUUAUAGCCACACAACCAAUCUCUGCUUCAGACUCUGGGUAAAUUACUACUGAGUAAGAGCUGGGCAUUUAGAAAGAUGUCAUUUGCAAUAGAGCAGUCCAUUUUGUAUUAUGCUGAAUUUUCACUGGACCUGUGAUGUCAUUUCACUGUGAUGUGCACAUGUUGUCUGUUUGGUGUCUUUUUGUGCACAGAUUAUGAUGAAGAUUAGAUUGUGUUAUCACUCUGCCUGUGUAUAGUCAGAUAGUCCAUGCGAAGGCUGUAUAUAUUGAACAUUAUUUUUGUUGUUCUAUUAUAAAGUGUGUAAGUUACCAGUUUCAAUAAAGGAUUGGUGACAAACACAGAA